GAGUGAGGCGUCGUCCGUACUGGAGGCUAGCUCUUGUCGCGGCCGCGGCGAGUUAACAUCGUUUUUCCAAUCUGUCCGCGGCUGCCGCCACCCAAGACAGAGCCAGAAUGUUCAGGAUGCUGAACAGCAGUUUUGAGGAUGACCCCUUCUUCUCGUGAGUUACGGGAGCCAGGAGUCCGGGGUCGCGCGGGAAUUAAGAGACCAUGCAAGCAAGAAGAGAAUGGCAUGAAAUAUAUAAAGUGUUGAGAGGAAAAAAACCCACUGACCUAGAAUUCUGUAUCCUGCAAAAUUAUCCUUUAAAAGUCAAGAAGAAAUAGACUGUCUCAGACAAACAAAAAUUUGGUGAAUUUGUUGACAGUAGACCUGCCUUGCAAGAAAUGUUAAAAGAAGUUCUUCAGAGAGAAGGAAAAUCAUACAAGUCAGAAACUCUGAUGUACAUUAAAAAAGCAAGAGCAUCAGAGAAUAAGUUAAGACAUACAGGUGGUCUUACUCUGCAGCAGCUGAAACUGAAGCACAAGAAGCCCUUGGAACUAUCAUCAGGACAUUGAGUCCAUUCUUGCACACCGAGAAAAUAUGCGACAGAUGAUAAGAAGUUUUUCUGAACCCUUUGGAAGAGACUUGCUCAGUAUCUCUGAUGGUAGAGGGAGAGCUCAUAAUCGUAGAGGACAUAAUGAUGGUGAAGAUUCUUUGACUCAUACAGAUGUCAGCUCUUUCCAGACAAUGGACCAAAUGGUGUCAAAUAUGAGAAACUAUAUGCAGAAAUUAGAAAGAAACUUCGGUCAACUUUCAGUGGAUCCAAAUGGACAUUCAUUUUGUUCUUCCUCAGUUAUGACUUAUUCCAAAAUAGGAGAUGAACCGCCAAAGGUUUUUCAGGCCUCAACUCAAACUCGUCGAGCUCCAGGAGGAAUAAAGGAAACCAGGAAAGCAAUGAGAGAUUCUGACAGUGGACUAGAAAAAAUGGCUAUUGGUCAUCAUAUCCAUGACCGAGCUCAUGUCAUUAAAAAGUCAAAGAACAAGAAGACUGGAGAUGAAGAGGUCAACCAGGAGUUCAUCAAUAUGAAUGAAAGUGAUGCUCAUGCUUUUGAUGAGGAGUGGCAAAGUGAGGUUUUGAAGUACAAACCAGGACGACACAAUCUAGGAAACACUAGAAUGAGAAGUGUUGGCCAUGAGAAUCCUGGCUCCCGAGAACUUAAAAGAAGGGAGAAACCUCAACAAAGUCCAGCCAUUGAACAUGGAAGGAGAUCAAAUGUUUUGGGGGACAAACUCCACAUCAAAGGCUCAUCUGUGAAAAGCAACAAAAAAUAAAUAGCCAUGCAUUUGAUUUGUUUAGUUUUGAUUGUUUUAACAGUUAGUAAUGGUGCUGGGUAAUAAGCAUAAGACCAAUCUCUUGCUGUUAAAUCAGUUCUGUCCUUGGCAACUUUCUUCUGAUAUCUGAAUGUUCAUGAAGGUCCUAGCUUUAUAUUGUCCCUCUUUUAGGAAUAAAAUUUUGAUUUUCAACAAUGUGAGUAAAUUGAGUCUAUUUAAUGUAAAACUCUUUAAAACAUACUAAUUUUUUAAAGCUUAUAUGCUUAUUUCGCUUCCCCAGUUGUUUUUGUGUUGGCUAAAUAUUCUUUUAUAUUUAUCAAGAUUGAUUGCAGAGCAGUUCUAUCACUUAUAAUUAGUUAUAAGAAAUUAUAAUGUUAAAAAAGUCUCAGUUUUUACUAACACUGUACUAGGGUGAUAUUAAUAAAGGUUUAAAUAAUUUAUCUCUAAUUUUAUAAUGUGUUGUAAAGCCAACUAGCUUAAAACUUUAAAAAUAAUAAAGCAAAACUACACUAGUACUCUUUUAUGAGAAAAUAGUUACUAUUUUGAUAAAGGGCAAGGAUAAUCAAAUAGUUCAUUUUCAGAGAAAAAUAUUUUAAAUUGCUAAUGUACAUGAUUGUUUUGGUUAUAAUUUAUUUAUAGAAUGUAUCUUUUCUAUAUUACAUUCUUAAUAUUCACCAGAUAUUAUAUUGACCAUUCUCUUUAACUUCUUAAUGUGGCAUAUUUCUACUCUCCUUUCCCACAAACAGCUUCAUCUGUCUCCAAGGUUAACAUUCUGAAGCUGGAGAGUCCUUGGAGAAACUCUGCUCAGCUUUUUUGUGACAUUUAGAAAAAUGCAUUUGGUAUUCUCCAAACCAGAAUGAUACAUUGUCUCAAAAUCUGUUAGACAGCUGAUGGGUGUUUUUGAGCAACGUCUUAAUAAUUCAGUUGUUUCUGUUUUAAUUAUACCAUUAAAAAUCAGCUUUAGCUUUUUAAUUCUAGAAUUUAAGCAUCAGUCUGUUCUUAUAAAAGUUAGGUUUGAAGUUUAUAAGAAUAUAAAAUCUUAACUCACAUUUGUUGUUUAAUAUUUCUGUCAAGGAAAAAAGCCCCCAAAAAUUGCUAUCACUCUAUAAUCCUAAGUAUUUUUCUUUUCAAUUUUGUAAGUAAAAUUAUAUGACUAUGUUCAUACUUCUCUAAUUUUUUAUAUAAUAUUUUUGUUAAUUUUACUAGUUUGUGUUUUAUGCCUUUAGUCAUUAAAAUAAAAUGCAAAUGUGUUAA